CUCACUCCGCCUGCCGGCUGGGAAACUAGGGCACCAGUACGAUAGUUCCGGCACCGGAAAAGAGGGCUGAUGACUGGGCCCGGGGGCCGCCGCAACGACCCUUGGGGCCGGCAAAGAGCCAGAGAGGGUGCUCACACUUCCAAGCACCCCACACCAAGGACAGGCUGGACGGCAAGGCGGAGACGCGGGGCUUGGGCCCUCAGACCGGGGACAGCAGGAGGUUGGGCCAAGGGCCAGGACUUCCCGUCACAAUUUCAUUUGUUGAUCCCGGCACCGCCAGGGGACUUUGUGCAACUGCCUGUGCCCGUCAUCCAGCAGCUCUACCACUGGGACUGUGGCCUGGCCUGCUCCAGGAUGGUGCUGCGGUACCUGGGCCAGCUGGACGACAGUGAGUUUGAGAGAGCCCUGCAGAAGCUGCAGCUGACCAGGAGCAUCUGGACCAUCGACCUGGCCUACCUGAUGCACCACUUUGGCGUGAGGCACCGCUUCUGUACCCAGACCCUGGGUGUCGACAAGGGCUACAAGAACCAGUCCUUCUACAGGAAGCACUUUGACACAGAAGAGACCCGGGUGAAUCAGCUGUUUGCACAAGCAAAGGCCUGCAAGGUGCUGGUGGAGAAAUGCACAGUGAGUGUGAAGGACAUCCAGGCGCACCUGGCUCAGGGCCAUGUGGCCAUCGUGCUGGUGAACUCGGGGGUGCUGCACUGUGACCUGUGCUCCAGCCCUGUCAAGUACUGCUGCUUCACCCCCAGUGGCCACCACUGCUUCUGCCGCACUCCUGACUACCAGGGCCACUUCAUCGUGCUGCGUGGCUACAACCGGGCCACUGGCUGCAUCUUCUACAACAACCCAGCCUAUGCCGACCCAGGAAUGUGCAGCACCAGCAUCAGUAACUUUGAGGAGGCCAGAACCAGCUAUGGCACAGAUGAGGACAUCCUCUUUGUCUACUUGGACAGCUGACAGCAGGAGCCUGGUGCGCCUAGGCCCUCGGACCCCAUCCCCACCCCAGCCGGGCCCGCUCAGGAUGCCCUGGCCCAGGCUUGGGGCUGCUGGGGUUGGAAUGUGGAACUGCAGCCUCAGCCCAUCUGGCAGAGUCCCAGGAACUCGGAGACUGGCACAGCUGCUUUGUCUGCCAGUGCCGUGUGUUGUCAUGUCACUCACCCCAAGCACCUGCUGGCUGCUGGAAGCAUACCCCAAGACCCCAAGCCUUGACUCCAGCUGCGCCCACAGGAAGUCCAGUCCCGACAGUGCCCUUGUUGCCUUUGAGCCAGAUCCAUGGCAAUGGUCUCCCCACAGACCGCAGGACUGAGCCUGGAGAGAGAAGUUGCUUGACGGAUGCCACUUGUCAGGACAGUAUGUGAGUGUCUGGAGACAGCAUAGCUGACCCCAAUCCCCCAGGGCUGAGGACCCCUCCAGGCCCCUCUCUCCUGGAAGUGCUGCAUAUGCCCCUGUGCCCAGUGGUUGAUGAUACCACCACCACCUGCCUACCCAUGGGCCCAAGUUUCUGUGGCUCAUUACAGGGCAUCUGACCCCUGCCACCCAGCAUAGACACACCUCACAGCUGCCCUGCCAUGCAGAGCCCUGGCCGCUGGAGACUCUUAAAGCCCCCACAGCCCUCCAGGUCCUCCAGCUCUGUCAGAUGGAGGGCUCUCGGGCCUAGAUCCCACUGGUAGGCCUCGUGGCUGGCAGCAGUGCUCUGGGAAUAAACAGCUGCCCUAGCCCCAGAGGGAUCCCUGCACCCAGGAGGCCUCCUGACACCAGCCAAAAUCCUGACAGCAGGGUCUGCCCUCUUGAGUGUGGGGAGCCCCUAGUCCUUUAAGGUUGGCUGCUAAGGCCUGUGCUCCAAAGCAACGGGCUGGGGCAGCCUGCAGCUGCCCACCCAACCUGGUCUUCACACCAGAUUGCACAGGAUACUGGGUCUUGUCUAUCUUGAUGGAGAAGAGGGGUUCCUGCCCAGGAUCUUACAACACAGCAAGUAGCAUAGAGCUCUUUCCUUCCUCUUUUUUGGGGAGGUUGGGGUCAGGGGUUGUUUCUUUGAGAUUUAAGUUUUCAUUUUUGAGGGGUAAUCACCUUCAAGUAAAACAGUAAUAGCAAGAGUGAAGGUACUUUGGAACCACUAACACCUCUGCACAGGGCAGUUAGCCAGCUCAAGUUCUUUUUCAGAGAAAGGGACUUGGCCAGUGGUUUAAGUACCUGCCCCUUCACCUCUCAGACGAGGCAGCUGACGAGGCAGCUGGCCCAGUCUUGGGAGUCUGCUCAGGACAGUGGUGGAGCUGGGUCUUGAACCCCAGUCUGCACCUAAAAAACUAAAGGAAAUGGAUUUUUUUUUUUUUUUUUGAGACGGAGACUCACUCUGUUGCCCAGACUGGAGUGCAGUGGCACGAUCUUGGCUUACUACAACCUCCGCCUCCUGGGUUCAAGCGAUCCUCCUGCCUCAGCCCCCCACUAGCUGGGACUACAGGCACAUGCCACCAUGCCCGGCUAAUUUUUUUGUAUUUUUAGUAGAGACCAGGCUUCGCCAUGUUGGCCAGGCUGGUCUCGAACCCCUGAGCUCAGGUGAUCCACCUGCCUCGGCCUCCCAAAGUGGGAAAUGGGUCAUUUUCAAAGGGGCAACAGUGAUACCAUCCCUGCACUCCUGGGUCCUGCUCUUCCAAUGCCCAAGGCAUGGCAUGGUGGCAGCUGUGCCCCCGCCCAUUGCUUUGGAGCACAGAUGACUCUGGGGGCAGAGGUGGGCUCUGUUUAGGAGGGCAGUGAGACCACCCAGCCAAAUUGCUUCUCAACCCUAGACAAAGCCUUUGGCCAAGAGGGAGGUGCUGUUAGUUGGGCAGCCCUUCUGGGUUUCAGAGACCGGUGUUGGCUCUAGACUGGUCUCAUCUCCAUUGCCUUAAUGCCAGGUGGCCCAGGAGUACCCAUGCACAGCAGCUGUGGGGUGUGGGCAUCUUCAGGUGGUGUUCUGGUAAAAUUGUUAGAAUAGCUGUAUGAAGGAAACCAGUGGGAGGAAAUGAAGUUUUCAGGAUGGUGGGAUGUGAUUUAGACAGUGCACAUGCUGUUAGGGCUGUCACUAGGGAGUGGCCUUCAUGGAGGGUGGUAACAGCACCUCAGUCCAGCCAAAAUGUUUAGAAACACUCAGUCUCUGGUCCCAGAGGAUGGCUUCUCAGGGCAUGCCACAAGUUAAAGGUCACCUUCCUGAAAGAUGAAUGAGAAAGCUGCCCAUUCUCAAGACUCAUCUGCCUAGGGAGGGUCACAGAGGCAGGAUGUAAGACACACUGUGUUGCAUUCUUGCACAAGUCAUGAAAAUGGAGCCAGAGAGCCUGGACAUCAGGGACUUUUGCCCACAGCACAUGACACCGACAGCUGCCCAGCCUGUUCACAUGCUGGGGACCAGCACAGCACCUGAAGCCAUGUGGGACAGUUGGGCUUUGUUCAUUCUAGCCACGGGGAUGAAAGGGAUCUUUUGCAUUGCAGAGAUUUUAUAUAUAUUUUGUUUGUAAUGAGCCAUUCUCAAUAAACAUUAUUCUCACUGCAAAA